GCCUCUCCCCUGGUUCCCGCACCCUGGCCGGCGGCUGCGAGCGCAGGGCCCAGCCCGGGAGCCGCUGGAGCAGGGCCUGCGAUGGAGCCUGCAGCCCCGGGUCGCGUCCCUCCCUGAGCGCCCCCGUCGGCGGCCAUGCUGCCCCGAGGGCGCCCCCGGGCGCUGGGGGCCGCCGCGCUGUUGCUGCUGCUGCUGCUGCUCGGAUUCCUCCUGUUCGGUGGGGACCUGGGGUGUGAGCGCCGCGAGCCUGGCGGGCGAGCGGGGGCCCCGGGAUGCUUCCCCGGCCCGCUCAUGCCACGUGUCCCCCCAGACGGGAGGCUGCGGAGAGCCGCCGCCCUCGACGGAGACCCGGGGGCCGGCCCCGGGGACCACAACCGCUCCGACUGCGGCCCGCAGCCGCCGCCGCCGCCCAAGUGCGAGCUCUUGCAUGUGGCCAUCGUGUGUGCGGGGCAUAACUCCAGCCGAGACGUCAUCACCCUGGUGAAGUCCAUGCUCUUCUACAGGAAAAAUCCACUGCACCUCCACUUGGUGACUGACGCCGUGGCCAGAAACAUCCUGGAGACGCUCUUCCACACAUGGAUGGUGCCUGCUGUCCGUGUCAGCUUUUAUCAUGCCGACCAGCUCAAGCCCCAGGUCUCCUGGAUCCCCAACAAGCACUACUCCGGCCUCUAUGGGCUAAUGAAGCUGGUGCUGCCCAGUGCCUUGCCUGCUGAGCUGGCCCGCGUCAUUGUCCUGGACACGGAUGUCACCUUCGCCUCUGACAUCUCGGAGCUCUGGGCCCUCUUUGCUCACUUUUCUGACACGCAGGCGAUCGGUCUUGUGGAGAACCAGAGUGACUGGUACCUGGGCAACCUCUGGAAGAACCACAGGCCCUGGCCUGCCUUGGGCCGGGGAUUUAACACAGGUGUGAUCCUGCUGCGGCUGGACCGGCUCCGGCAGGCUGGCUGGGAGCAGAUGUGGAGGCUGACAGCCAGGCGGGAGCUCCUUAGCCUGCCUGCCACCUCACUGGCUGACCAGGACAUCUUCAACGCUGUGAUCAAGGAGCACCCGGGGCUAGUGCAGCGUCUGCCUUGUGUCUGGAAUGUGCAGCUGUCAGAUCACACACUGGCCGAGCGCUGCUACUCUGAGGCGUCUGACCUCAAGGUGAUCCACUGGAACUCACCAAAGAAGCUUCGGGUGAAGAACAAGCAUGUGGAAUUCUUCCGCAAUUUCUACCUGACCUUCCUGGAGUACGAUGGGAACCUGCUGCGGAGAGAGCUCUUUGUGUGCCCCAGCCAGCCCCCACCUGGUGCUGAGCAGUUGCAGCAGGCCCUGGCACAACUGGACGAGGAAGACCCCUGCUUUGAGUUCCGGCAGCAGCAGCUCACUGUGCACCGUGUGCAUGUCACUUUCCUGCCCCAUGAACCGCCACCCCCCCGGCCUCACGAUGUCACCCUUGUGGCCCAGCUGUCCAUGGACCGGCUGCAGAUGUUGGAAGCCCUGUGCAGGCACUGGCCUGGCCCCAUGAGCCUGGCCUUGUACCUGACAGACGCAGAAGCUCAGCAGUUCCUGCAUUUCGUCGAGGCCUCACCAGUGCUUGCUGCCCGGCAGGACGUGGCCUACCAUGUGGUGUACCGUGAGGGGCCCCUAUACCCCGUCAACCAGCUUCGCAACGUGGCCUUGGCCCAGGCCCUCACGCCUUACGUCUUCCUCAGUGACAUUGACUUCCUGCCUGCCUAUUCUCUCUACGACUACCUCAGGGCCUCCAUUGAGCAGCUGGGGCUGGGCAGCCGGCGCAAGGCAGCACUGGUGGUGCCGGCAUUCGAGACCCUGCGCUACCGCUUCAGCUUCCCCCAUUCCAAGGUGGAGCUGUUGGCCUUGCUGGAUGCGGGCACUCUCUACACCUUCAGGUACCACGAGUGGCCCCGAGGCCACGCACCCACAGACUAUGCCCGCUGGCGGGAGGCUCAGGCCCCGUACCGUGUGCAAUGGGCGGCCAACUAUGAACCCUACGUGGUGGUGCCACGAGACUGUCCCCGCUAUGAUCCUCGCUUUGUGGGCUUCGGCUGGAACAAAGUGGCCCACAUUGUGGAGCUGGAUGCCCAGCUCUCAGGGGCUACAGGGUAAGCCUGUUCUCUGGAGCUGCACCUUCCCCGCAGGCCAGGCAAGCCAGGCAGCCACUGCUCCUCUGCCCCACCCUGCAGGAAUAUGAGCUCCUGGUGCUGCCCGAGGCCUUCACCAUCCAUCUGCCCCACGCUCCAAGCCUGGACAUCUCCCGCUUCCGCUCCAGCCCCACCUAUCGUGACUGCCUCCAGGCCCUCAAGGACGAAUUCCACCAGGACUUGUCCCGCCACCAUGGGGCUGCUGCCCUCAAAUACCUCCCAGCCCUGCAGCAGCCCCAGAGCCCUGCCCGAGGCUGAGGCUGGGCCGGCGCUGCCCCUCAUCUUAGCAUUGGGCAGACACCAGGGCAACCUGCCCUCCGCCAUCCCUGCUAUUUAAAUUAUUUAAGGUCUCUGGGAAGGGCUGGGGCAGAGCAUCUGUGGGGUGGGGUCUUCCCCUUGCUGCUAUUGUAUGGCUGGGGACUGGUCUCUCUCUGCCCCAGCCAGUUUGGGGCUGGUUCCCCCAUCUUGAAUUGUUUAUCCCUUUUUCAUAAUUAAAGUUUUAAAACAUC